AUCGCGCAUCUGGUUGCCAGGGAAACAGCGGUCCCACAGGCAGGAGGGAUCUGGACCGGCGGCUUCUUCCACUACCAGAGAGGCUGAGGUGGCGGGAGAGACCCCUCUCCUCUGGGGGUAAGUGGCUGGCGCGGCGAGUGUCUGCGGCGCGCUUCUGCGGCCAUCUGCGCCCUGACUGACGGCGGCCAGUUCCUCGAGGAGGCCCGGCGGGAAGGAUUUCAAUGGAUAUUAUAAAGGGAAACCUAGAUGGAAUUUCAAAACCAGCUUCAAAUUCAAGAAUACGCCCUGGGAGCAGAAGUUCAAAUGCUUCUUUGGAGGUGCUCUCAACAGAACCAGGAUCCUUCAAGGUCGAUACUGCAAGCAACUUGAACUCUGGUAAAGAGGACCACUCCGAAAGCAGUAAUACAGAGAACAGAAGAACUAGUAAUGAUGAUAAGCAGGAAAGCUGCUCUGAGAAAAUAAAAUUGGCUGAAGAGGGAUCAGAUGAAGAUCUGGAUUUGGUUCAACAUCAGAUAAUCUCUGAGUGUUCAGAUGAACCCAAAUUAAAAGAAUUAGAUUCUCAACUUCAAGAUGCUAUUCAGAAGAUGAAAAAACUUGAUAAAAUAUUGGCAAAGAAACAACGCAGAGAAAAAGAAAUUAAGAAGCAAGGUCUAGAAAUGAGAAUAAAGCUGUGGGAAGAAAUUAAGUCUGCAAAAUAUAGUGAAGCUUGGCAAAGUAAAGAGGAGAUGGAAAAUACAAAAAAAUUUUUAUCUUUGACUGCUGUUUCUGAAGAAACUGUUGGUCCUUCUCAUGAGGAGGAAGACACCUUUUCCUCAGUGUUUCAUACUCAAAUCCCUCCAGAAGAAUAUGAAAUGCAGAUGCAGAAACUCAAUAAAGAUUUUACCUGUGAUGUGGAAAGAAAUGAGUCAUUGAUCAAAUCAGGAAAGAAACCUUUCUCGAAUACAGAAAAGAUUGAGCUCAGGGGUAAACACAACCAGGAUUUUAUUAAGAGAAACAUUGAGUUGGCCAAGGAAUCAAGAAACCCAGUGGUUAUGGUUGACAGAGAGAAGAAAAGGCUGGUUGAGCUUUUGAAGGACUUGGAUGAGAAAGAUUCCGGGCUCUCCAGUUCUGAGGGUGAUCAGUCUGGCUGGGUGGUCCCAGUAAAAGGAUAUGAACUUGCAGUCACCCAGCAUCAGCAGCUUGCUGAAAUUGAUAUAAAACUCCAAGAACUCUCUGCAGCCUCCCCUACAAUUUCCAGUUUUUCUCCAAGACUUGAAAAUCGGAAUAAUCAGAAACCUGACCGUGAUGGUGAAAGAAAUAUGGAAGUAACUCCAGGAGAAAAGAUACUUAGGAACACCAAAGAGCAACGCGAUCUGCAUAAUCGGCUGAGAGAGAUUGAUGAAAAGCUGAAAAUGAUGAAGGAAAAUGUGUUAGAGUCCACAUCAUGUCUCUCUGAAGAACAGUUAAAGUGUCUUCUGGAUGAAUGCAUACUUAAACAAAAAUCCAUCAUUAAACUUUCUUCAGAAAGAAAAAAGGAAGACAUUGAGGACGUAACACCUGUGUUCCCCCAGCUUUCCAGGUCCAUCAUCUCUAAAUUGCUAAAUGAAUCAGAAACAAAGGUCCAGAAAACUGAGGUAGAAGAUGCAGAUAUGCUUGAGAGUGAAGAAUGUGAAGCUUCUAAAGGCUACUAUCUCACUAAAGCCUUGACUGGACAUAACAUGUCAGAAGCUCUUGUCACUGAAGCAGAGAAUAUGAAAUGCCUUCAAUUUUCCAAGGACGUUAUUAUUAGUGACACAAAAGACUAUUUUAUGUCGAAGACUCUUGGCAUUGGGAGACUGAAAAGGCCCUCCUUCUUAGAUGAUCCACUGUAUGGUAUCAGUGUGAGCCUUUCAUCAGAAGACCAACAUCUGAAACUCAGUUCUCCAGAGAAUACAAUAGCAGAUGAGCAGGAGACUAAAGAUGCAGCAGAAGAAUGUAAAGAACCCUAAUCAAGGACUUGCUGGGUGUGCUUUUCAGAAAGUUGAGUUUGGGCCUUUUAGAUUGCAUCAAAUAAAGAUGAGCUACUUUAAAAGACAGUCUGCGGUACUAUUUGAAGAGAGAUGGUUUAGUUACAAGUCAGUAACUUAGAUUCAUGAGAAAAUUUUGUGUUGACAUUCCAUAAGAUGAGUUGGCAUUAGAAUUGGAAGUCCAGUUUAUUUCUGAAUCAAAAAAUGAGCGGGCUAUUGUGCUGCCUUUAAUAAAAUUUGAGUGAUGUAUACAUAACAUUGUUUUUGCUGGCACAUGUUCAUCCACUGAUACUGAAUAACAUUAAUGAUUGUUUAUAUGGAAUUUCCUUGACUUUUUAAAAUGAGGAAUUCUAUAGCUACUAUUUUCAGAGGUAUUGAUAGGCAGUUUCUUUUUCCAGACACUAUUUCAGUUUACUAUUUGUUCAUUUAAAAUAGCAAUUGUUCAUGCUGAUGUCAAUGUGCUACGUAUAAUUUAUCUUGAUGCCAAGAGUUUUGCUGUGGGAUGGAAGUAUAAGUUAAAAGUUGUGAUUUUAGAUUCUCAUAGGAAUGCCAUGAGGCACACUCUGUGUUUUAGGGUUUGGGUGGGAAGAAUCAGAGGGCAAAGGUGAUAUGGGUGAGAAUUUGUUGUGGGGCAGAGAGGGGCCAGUGUUGUCCGUCAGCGUUUCAGAGGAGUUCAGCUUUCUAAAUCUAUGCUUUUCUGGUAUUUGAUGUUUGUAUGUAUGAGAGAGAGAGAGAGAGAGAGAAAGAAGGAGGAGGGAGGGGAGGGGAGGGUAGGAAGGAAAAAGGGGAGGGAAGAGGGAGACAGAAAGAAACACAGAGUAAAAUUAUUUCUAGACUUGCACUGCAAAGGGCUUAUGACUUUAUAGUUUGCUUCUGCCAAUGAUAUUUGGGACAUAGUGAGCCUUUCUGUUAUUUAGGUAAGGGGGAAGAAAAUAGAGUUAUUUUAAGUAAUGAAUUCUGCCAUAAAAGAGGUGGGACCAUUCACAGCAUGUCAACUGAAGGUAACUCUAACAAGGACUGGUAACUAAGUCUGUAACGUAAUUCAACAAAAAGCUUCCGGAUUUUUUUUAAAAAGUCACCCUGAUUUAGAUAGAAAGUGUUAUUAAAAAUAGAUGUUUUUAUUUUGGAUUUCCCUUUAGGGCUUAGUGUUUGUCCGGAACAAGGUGAAACCCCGUCUUUACUAAAAAUACAGAAUUAGCCAGGCUUGGUGGCGGGCGCUUGUAGUCCCAGCUACUUGGGAGGCUGAGGCAGGAGGGAGAAUUGCUUGAACCGGGGAGGCAGAGGUUGCAGUGAGCCGAGAUUGUGUCACUGCACUCCAGCCUGGGCGACAGAGCAAGACUUCAUCUCAAAAAUAAAAAGAAAAAGAAAUUAUAGAAGAGAGAGAGAGCCAAUUUAUUUAAGGAAUGAAUUCAGGAGCUUAAUACUGGAGGCUUUUCUACAUGUGACUCUUUAGAAAAAAAAAAACUGCUGGCACCACCUUUAUUGUAUGUACAUUCUUAUAAGACCUGGAGUUUAUUGCUCUUCACUCGAGCUCUCCCACAACACAUGACAAUAAACUGUUGGAGGAGGAAAAAAGCUAUCAUCUCGAUGACAUAAUUUUAAUUUUUAACAAGUCCUUUAUUUCAGUACAACCUGAUUAUUUGAAGGUCAGUCUUAGGGUGAAACUGGAACAUGCCUGGAAGAAAAGCUCCUCUUUCCAGUCACUUUUUCUGUCUUAUCUUGGUAUUUUCAAUCAGUUUUGCUUCACUAUCCAAGAAUGAAUUAGAAUUAUCUCCCAGCACUUCAAACGUUGAACUCUUCUGAUAAUGAAUGAUGGUAUUUAAUUCUUUGCCAUUUCAAAGAAUUAUUUCCUUCACAUCAGUUUUCCUAACUCCACAGCUAUUAUCAACACUUUCUAGUUCCUGCUUCUUCACCUUGGUACUAUAAAAUGAUUUGGCAAUUUACAUUUGUAUGUGAUCAUGGCUACUCAGAAAGAUGAGUAUUUAUAGAAUGAGAGUGAAAAUCAACAAGGAAGAUUUUAUCUCACCCAGCCAGUCCUUUCUAGUGUUUAAUAGACCUCAAAGCCAGACCUUUAACCUACUCAUAAAAUUUCUUCUUUGAUCUGUUUUCAUUAAAACUGGAAAUUAACUGGUCAGUAUUCCACAUUCAUAAUUAGCCCAUCCAAAAAUCAAGGUCUGCUUAUUGGUACACUUGGGCCUUUUCUUCACAUGAUAAUUUGUAUUUAGACACACACGCAUUUAUGGAUUCCUUCCAAAUUUUACAUUUUUUAGUCUUCUUUUUUGAUUAAACUUAUUAUUCCUUCUUCAAGAGGAGGUAUCUGUAAUGCUUGGCUCAACAUUGCAAGGACAGCUCCUCCCUCAUCCACAUUUACUUCCGAAGUGUCUCCACAACAUGCAAUCGUGUUGCCCACCCAAGGCAUCAUUCGUGGGUCAGAAAAUGUCGCUGUGAGAGUUGCGUGUGCUUCAGUGUUUUUCCCUUUGUUUUCAUACUGCACUUUGAAAAGGAUUCAAUGACAUCUAAUGACCUUAAUAAGAAAUUUUAUUCUUAUGGGGGCCCUUGACUUAGGGAUAAUUUCUCUUUUAUAUGUUUUUGAUAUGGCAGGCUAAUGUAUCAUUUUGUUCUUUUAUUCCACAAACGCAGCAAAUUCUAAGCCUAGGCCUGAGCAACUCAGUCUUUCUCAAUCACAUACAAACUGUGAAUGUUGCUAUGACUUACUGUAAUUUAUUUUUGUAUAUGCUAUAUUGAUUUAUGAAUGGUAUUUACGCAUAUACUUCAUGACAUAAAGCCAGUAGAGAACAAAUAAGCAUGGAUACAGUAAGUAUAAAUAUAAAUUUCCAUAUGAUUUAU